CAAGAAAGGCCCAAACAAAGCUAAUCUUUUGUCUUUUUGGUAAUGGCCAUUUUAACUGGUAUGAGGUGACUGAGGUGAUAUUUCAUUGUGAUUUUGAUUUUCAUUUUCUUAAUGAUUAGUGAUGUUGAACAUUUUUUCAUAUACCUGUUGGCCAUUUGCUUGUCUUCUUUUGAGAAGUCUAUUCAGGUCUUUUGACCAUGUUUUUUUUUUUUUUAAUUAGAAAAAUUAUUUAUUUCUGCUCCUUUCAUACAUCUUAUUGUUCAGGAAACAGUCUUACAUACAUAUCUGAAAUAAUCUACCGUCACACACUCUAGUUAAAGGCAAAGCACCAUAGGUAAACCUGAUCAGCUGUCCAGAGUUCUGAGCUUAUGGAAUCUUGCUUCUUGAUUUUACGUUAAUUUCUGAAAACAGAAACGCCAUCUCCAAAAGGUGUUAAGGGGGUUGUAAAAAAUAAUCACUUUAUUUGAUAUUACAGCUGUAAAUAUGGAGCUCUUUUUUUUUCUUUUUUACAGUUUUUUUUUUUUUUUUUAAUUUUUUUUUAUUGAUCAUUCUUGGGUGUUUCUCACAGAGGGGGAUUUGGCAGGGUCAUAGGACAAUAGUGGAGGGAGGGUCAGCAGAUAAACAAGUGAACAAAGGUCUCUGGUUUUCCUAUGCAGAGGACCCUGCGGCCUUCCGCAGUGUUUGUGUCCCUGGGUACUUGAGAUUAGGGAGUGGUGAUGACUCUUAACGAGCAUGCUGCCUUCAAGCAUCUGUUUAACAAAGCACAUCUUGCACCACCCUUAAUCCAUUUAACCCUGAGUGGACACAGCACAUGUUUCAGAGAGCACAGGGUUGGGGAUAGGGUCACUGAUCAACAGGAUCACAAGGCAGAAUAAUUUUUCUUAGUACAGAACAAAAUGAAAAGUCUCCCGUGUCCACCUCUUUCUACACAGACAUGGCAACCAUCCGAUUUCUCAAUCCUUUCCCCGCCUUUCCCCCCUUUCUAUUCCACAAAACCGCCAUUGUCAUCAUGGCCCGUUCUCAAUGAGCUGUUGGGUACACCUCCCAGACGGGGUGGUGGCUGGGCAGAGGGGCUCCUCACUUCCCAGUAGGGGCGGCCGGGCAGAGGCGCCCCUCACCUCCCGGACGGGGCGGCUGGCCGGGCGGGGGGCUGACCCCUCCACCUCCCUCCCGGACGGGGCGGCUGGCUGGGCGGGGGGCUGACCCCCCCACCUCCCUCCCGGACGGGGCGGCUGGCCUGGCGGGGGCUGACCCCCACCUCCCUCCCGGAUGGGGUGGCUGCCGGGCGGAGGGGCUCCUCACUUCUCAUAUGGGGCAGUUGCCAGGCGGAGGGUCUCCUCACUUCUCAGACGGGGCGGCUGGGCAGAGACGCUCCUCACCUCCCAGACGGGGUCGCGGCCGGGUAGAGGCGCUCCUCACAUCCCAGACGGGGCGGCGGGGCAGAGGCGCUCCCCACAUCUCAGACGAUGGGCGGCCGGGCAGAGACGCUCCUCACUUCCUAGAUGGGAUGGCGGCCGGGAAGAGGCGCUCCUCACUUCCUAGAUGGGAUGGCGGCCGGGCAGAGACGCUCCUCACUUUCCAGACUGGGUAGCCAGGCAGAGGGGCUCCUCACAUCCCAGACGAUGGGCGGCCAGGCAGAGACGCUCCUCACUUCCCAGACGGGGUGGCGGCCGGGCAGAGGCUGCAAUCUUGGCACUUUGGGAGGCCAAGGCAGGCGGCUGGGAGGUGGAGGUUGUAGCGAGCCGAGAUCACGCCACUGCACUCCAGCCUGGGCACCAUUGAGCACUGAGUGAACCAGACUCCAUCUGCAAUCCCGGCACCUCGGGAGGCCGAGGCUGGCGGAUCACUCGCAGUUAGGAGCUGGAGACCAGCCCGGCCAACACAGCGAAACCCCGUCUCCACCAAAAAAAUACGAAAACCAGUCAGGCAUGGUGGCGCGCGCCUGCAAUCGCAGGCACUCGGCAGGCUGAGGCAGGAGAAUCAGGCAGGGAGGCUGCAGUGAGCCGAGAUGGCAGCAGUACAGUCCAGCUUCGGCUCGGCAUCAGUGGGAGACCGUGGAAAGAGAGGGAGAGGGAGACCGUGGGGAGAGGGAGACCGUGGGGAGAGGGAGAGGGAGAGGGAGAGGGCUUUUGACCAUUUUUAAACAGGGUUAUUUGUUUUCUUACUAUUAAGUUGAGUUCCUUUUAUAUUUUAGAUAUUAAACCUUUGUUGGAUGUAUACUUUGCAAAUAUAAUAUUUUCUCCCAUUCUAUAGGUUGUCGCUUCACUAUCGGUUGUUUCCUUUGCUGUGCAGAAGCUUUUUAGUUUGAUGUAGUUUGAUUUGCCCAUUGUUUGCUUUUGUUGCCUGUGCUUUUGAAGUCUUGUUCAUAAACUUCUUGCCCAUAUAAAUGUAAUGAAGCAUUUCUCCUGUGUUUCCUCUAGCAGUUUCAUAGUUUCAGGUCUUAAAUCUAUGUCUUUAAUUCAUCUUGAGUUGAUUUGUGUAUAUGGUGGGAGAUAAGGGUUUAAUUCAUUCUUCUGCAUGUGGAUUUUCAGUUUUCCCAGCAUCGUUUAUUGAAAGACUGUACUUUCUUUUCAAUAAAUGUGUGUUCUUGGUGCCUUUGUUGAAUAUCAGUUGGCUGUAAAUGUGUGGAUUUAUUCCUGGGUUCUCUGUUCCAUUGAUCUAUCUGUUUUUAUACCAGUACCAUGCUGUUUUUAUAACUUUAGUUUUAUGGCAUAUUUUGAAGUCAGGUAUUAUGAUGCCUCCAGCUUUGUUCUUUUUGCUCAAGAUUGCUUUGGCUAUUCAAGGUCUUUUGUGGUUACAUACGAAUUUUAGGAUUUUUUUUUCUAUCUGUGAAGAAUGUCAUUGGUAUUUUGAUAGGAAUUGCACUGAAUCUGCAGAUUGCUUUGGACGGUAUGAACAUUUAAGAAAUAAUUCUUUCAAUCCAUGAACACAGGAUAACUUUCCAUUUAUUUGUGUCUUCAGUUUCUUUCAUCAGUGUUUUAUAGUUUUCAUCCUAGAGAUUUUUCACCAUGGUUAAGUUUAUUUCUAGAUAUAUAUAUAUAUAUUUUUUUUUAAUUGUAUUGUAAAUGGGAUUUUCUUGAUUUCUUUUUCAUAUAGUUCACCAUUAAUGUAUAGAAAUGAUACUGGUUUAUGGCUGUAAUCCCAGCACUUUGGGAGGCCAAGGCAGGUGAGUUGCUUGAGCUCGCGAGUUUGCCACCAGCCUGAGCAACAUGGCAAAACCCUUUCUCUACAAAAAAUACAAAAGUUAGCCAGGUGUGGUGGUCCCAACUACUUGGGAGGCUGAGGUGGGAGGAUUGGUUGAGCCCAGGGAGUUGAGGCUGCAGUGAGCUGUGAUUGCAACACUGCACUUCAGCGUGGGCAACAGAGUGAGAUCUUGUCUCAAAAAAAAGAAAUAAUACUAGUUUUUGUUUGUAGAUUUUGUAUCCUGAAACUUUACUGAAUGUUUUUUAGUUCGAACAGUUUUUUUGGUGGAGUCUUUAGGAUUUUCUCUACUUAUGAUCGUGUCAUCUGUAAACAGAGACAGUUAACUUCCUCCUUUCCGAUUUAGAUGCCUUUUCUUUCUCUUGCCUAAUUGCCUAAUUACAGCAUGUUCCUAUUCUGUAAAUGUUCAAUGAACUAGAGAAUGAUUCUUGGGUAGUUAAUAUUGUCAAUGUUGAUGAACUCUUUUCCUUCGCUGAAAGCAGCUACUUUGUUGGAGGUUUCAAUUCUGCGUGGCAAUUUGCAGCAUUUCUAGUGGUACUGCUCCACAUUUUACAGCUUUAUGAAGAAGGUGUUUACUUUUUUUGAAAUUACCUUGAGACAUUUCAAACUGUGCAGAAGAUAUAUGCACAAAAGCAAAUGUCUUGCAGUUUGCUAUAGCCACUUAUACAUCAUCUGGCUCUUGAAUAGCUUUAAUUCAGCUGUUGAAUCUCACUUGAAUUUGAGCAAAACCUUCAUCUUUAUAUGUAUCUGGACAAAUUACUUCAAUUGCUUGACAGUAAUGACCAAUCAAUUUAUUUAAAAUAGUAUCAUUUAGUAGGACAGUGUUUUUCUCUGGUUUGAGCAACGAAUUCAACCAGUCCUCUGGGUUGAUCAUCAUCAUCAUCAUCAUUUGGUUAUCAGUUCCUGAGUUAUUUUUACCAGGGAGUUUUAUACCUUUAGACAGCUAUUUUGAAUUAUCUCAGGAAUGUCAUAUAUCUCUGCCUCUUUAGAGUCAGUCACUGGCACUUUGUCUGUUUGGUGACAUCAUGUUUCCCUGACUGUUCUUCAUCUUUGUAGUUAUACAUUGAUAUCUGUGCAUUGAAUAUGUAGGUAUUUAUAAACAGUCUUUGCAAUCUGGCUUUGUCUGUGAUUGUCCUUGUAUAGUAGGUCUGUCCAGAAAUUGUAAGCAUACUGUCUUUUUUGGUCUUUAAGCCCGUGAACGCUACAGCCCGUGUAGUGCCAAAUGGUGCCCUAAGCCCAGGUUCCCUGCAGUCCACUCUGUGAUUUGUUUGUUGACUGCUGUGAGCCCCACCCCCAUUCUUUGUUUCUAAUUUACACCUAGCAGGCUAACCCUGCUGGCACCUGCAGUGCUUCCAGGGGGAAAGGACCAUAGUGUGCCCCUGUGAAGAGUCUCAGAAUGGUGCGGAAGGUGAAUGCCCACCUCCCGCUCUCUUUUCCCACUGUAGAAACUGAUUCCAGAGAAAUUCUCCAAGUGCGGUGCUAUGUGGGCUUGCGGGAGAGGUGUUAUGAUCAAACAGAACCAUUCUCUUUACCCUCUGUUCAUGGUUUUUCUUGGCUCUGUGGUCCAGUGAGUUGUCACAGCUUCACUCCCAAUUUCUGGGAUAUUCAGGGCAAUAAUCUUGCCACUGGGUAUUUGCUAGUUGAAAUUAUGUGGUAGGGAGAGAAGCCAGUAAGCUUCACUUCUCCGUUUGGCUGAUGUCACUCUCGAAUUCUGUACUUUCAUACGGAUUGUAAUAGGGAGGGUCUAAAAGGAAGCUUCAGUUUUGGAUUUUUAGAGCUUCUUCUAAGUACAAUUGUUGAAUCAAGAGGUAAAAAUGGUAUGUUAUAACUGGAAAUACGCUGAGAUUAAAAAGGAGAUAAAUUAGCCCCAUUGGGACAGUGCUAUUGGGAAUGUGAAUUGAUACCACUUUCCUGGAGUCUAGUUUAGUAUUUAUUUUAUAUGUAAUGCCUGAAAAGAUGUGUGUCUCCUUUGACUCAAUACUUAUAGGAAUUUACACAAAGGUUAUAAUCAAAGAUUAUAGAACUGUUAUACUGGAAAAACACGAAAUAUUCUAAUUAUGAAUUAAUUGGGGAUUGGUUAAAUAAACUAUGGUUUGAUAUGCUCUAAAAAUAAUGUUACAGAAAAAAGUGUACUGAUAUGGCAAAAUGUAUGACUUAUAGUUAAAAAAGCAGGUUAGAUGUUGAUAGAUACAGUAUGAUAGAAAAAGAUCAGGAAGGUAUAUGCUGACAUUUAAAUCUGGAUAUUUAUGAGUGUUUUUUUUAUUUCAAUCUUUGUACAUGCAUGUAUUUUCUAGAAAUUGUAUUACUAUCUUUGUAAUAAAGUAAAUUAUUUUUAAGGGACUAAAUAAUAAAUAUUUGUUACUUGAGUGCCUUACACAUUCACUCGGCAAUUACAGUUUCCCGAACAUUGGACUUCAGACUCUUUUCACAGCACAUCCUUAUUUUCAUAAAUAGAAAAUUAAACUUUUUAUUUGUCAUUUUGAUGUUAUGCCAGGUUUAGAAUACUGGAGUCUCGAUCAAUAAGGUGGCACCACAUUGCAGAAUCAUCUCUUUUUACCAUGGGCCCAACAUGGAUGAGGAUCAAUCAGUGUCUGUAACAGUCUUUGCAGUGAGGGCAGAGUGACCAGUUAUUAAGUUGUAGGCUAAAAGAUCCUGGGAGAGACCAGCCACGCACAGGACUUCACAAAUCACUGGACAGUAAGGAAGAUGACCCUGUGGGUAGCACGAGAAAAUGUAGCCGCCUUCCUGGAAUCUAGUUCCUAUUCGCCUGUAGCACCAAAUGAACCAAUCUUACAACCAUAACCAGCAUAUGUAGCUUGGAAAGAUGCUGAAUUCCACACCCUAAGAUCUGGGAAUGGAUUUUGGCUCUUUCCAGCGUCCUAGUCUGGGGCAAGUCAUUCAGCCUCUUGAGACAGUUUCUCUAACAGUGACUAAACAUGCUGACCACCUGUGGUGGUUGGAAUAAGAGAAAAUAGCAUUACUCAUUGGCAGGUUUCUAAAUUGGGAAGCGUAAAAUGUGAGCAUUUAUAAGCGGUCUUAGUCUGUGUUGUGUGGCUAUAGCUGAUUCCCACAGACUGAGUCAUUUAUAAAGAAAAGAGUAAUUACAGUUUUAGGGGCUGGGGUGUCCAAAGUAAGGUAAGGGGAUGCAUCUGGUGAAGGCCUCCUUGCUGUAUUGUCCCCUGGCAGAAGGGCACAAGGCAGAAGUGGGUGCAGGAGACAGAAAGGAGGCAAGAGGGGCAGACCAUCUUUGAUAACAACUCAUUCUCCUGGUAACAGCAUUAAGCCAUCAUGAGAGCAGAGUCCUUGUGACUUCAUCACUUCUCAUCAGGCUCUGCCUCCCAACACCACUGCAGAGGACCAAGCUUCUAACUUAUGAAUUUAGGGGACACACUUAAACCAUAACAUAAGCCUUACCAAACAAAACAAGCAAAAAUUGGCUUUUUUCUCAGUGAAAAUACGCUGCUAACCAGAGGCUGCCAGUUCACGGCAGCACACAGUGCAGACUGGGUGACUUCCAUGGCUCUUCCGAGGCUCAUAGAGGUUUGGUUGGCGUGUCUUAGCGCACCAUGACAUCAUCCAGUGACCUUAGGGCUCAAACCUUGUGACCAGACAGCCCUGUGUUUCUAACCUCAAGCUAUUUAAAAAUUUAAAGGAGGCUACAUAUAUACACUAACCACUUUUUACCAUACUAGUUUCAAUUUAAAAUUAUCUUUUUGGUUAUCUUCCUUGCUGAGAGAAAAUUCUAGUGAAGCCUUCUGGGGGAGGAUCCUCCCCUUACAGGGGAAGAAAAACAUGACCAGACAGAAGUGAGAACCAGAACAGAGUGGAGGGCAUCUACCUUGUGUUUUUGUCUUUUCUCUGUUCACUUCUUUCACUGUUUGCAAAUAAACCCUGCCAAGGAGGCAGAGCACAUAAGGGGCCCUCGUGAGGGAAGUGCUUGAUGGGAUGCUGGACUUCCUCAUUAACACUUCACCUAGUUCAAAUUUGGCCUUCCCACAGCAGCUCCUACCUGGGGCUUUACCAGUUUUUGGAGCAUGCAGUCUUAAAUCUAGAAAGAAAUGCCCAGUGUGAUUCUUAGAUGUUUGGUGGCUUAACCUGUCCCAAAUGACAGGUGGGCCUCCCUUCACACUGGACAGGUCUGAAAUAACCAAGAGAAACAGUGGUGCUCCAACUCAGCUCCAUGGGGAAGCUGAGAGGGACCAUGGGACUUGUCCUGGGUCUGCCUUGGCAUGUACCAUCAUACGAUCUGGGCUCACAUAAGUAGCAGUCCUUUCCUAAGAGGAUUCUAUUCAUACUUCAUGAAAUACCAGUUGUCUAUAUCAAAUAAUCAGUGUGGAGAAACCACUCCAGACGAAAGGACACCUUGAUGGAAACAAGGUGGGCAGGUGAGGGUGAGGAAGCUGAGAUGAUACGGAUAAUUGUAUACUACUCAAAAUAAGUGCUUGAGGGCCUAAAACAUUACCCCAUGUAAUACAUGUGUUAUGCUUUUCUUAACAAUUGCAUUGGAACAAGAUAAAUGCAGAGGUGGUUAUGGCAAUUCCCUAUUUGUAAUGUACUUUUGAGACAGAAAAAUCAAAGUGAUCACCAAACUGUAGUGCUGAAAGAUGAUUCCUACUGUGAUCAUCGCAUUCCUUCAGUGGAAUUGCUGCAUGUGACUUUGCAGAGAGAACAGUUAGGGUAUGGUUAUGUUCCCCUACACUCCAAGUGGCCAAAGGACCCAAGGCAUUUGGGGGCAGCCUAUCAAGGUAUUUAAAUAUCAAGCCAUGAUAUUUAAUUUUAUUUUGAAGCCAAUGGAAAGCACGGAAAACUACAGAAGAGAGAGGUGCCAUUUAUAAUUCAAAUUAUUGAGGAUUUUAUAUAAGACAGAGUACCUACUUUUAGUCCCAGGUAUAGCAAAUUUGUCUUUUCUAACUUGACAAUGGCUUUAAAAGUGUACCAUGAUGCCCUUCCACUGCAAAUUACAGGGCACUCAGCUAUUUUUCACAAAAUCAUGAUACUUCAAUAACUAUGUUGUUUUUCUUUAGUGGAGCUACUAUUGAGCCUCACAGAUGAUUGACACAUAUUUCCCUGCAAAUUAACAUCACUUAGGACAUACUUAUCUCAGAGAAAACGGCCCAGAAGCAUAUUGGGGUGAAGGGAGGCUAAGGCCCCAGAGCUCUUCUGGGCAUGAGAUUUCUUUCUCAGGGGGUGCUUAUGAUUGGCUGCUUGUCCCAAGAUGCUAAUGGAGGCAGGGAAGGCUCACUGCUCCAGCCCAUGGGGCGGAGCAAGGCCAGUCCCUGUUGCUUCGGGUUCCAUUUAUGGGCUUUCUACCUGUGCUCACUUCCCCAAAGCCACCCCUGAUUUGAAUGCUGAUCAGCAGCCCCAUUGGAGCAGCCUGCUUGCAAAUGGGGUGGAGGGGGCUGAUCGCAGCCUUGCCCCUGCUCUCCUUGGUGCAGCCUGCUCUGGGAACCAGCUCAAAGGAUGAGGAUGUAGGAAGAAGCUGGUCUGCUGACUGUCAUACUUGUGACCAGCUUGCACAGGACAUGGCCGAGGAGGCAGCCCAGAACAUUUCUGAUGACCAGGAAAGGUGUCUCCAGGCUGCCUGCUGCCUUUCCUUUGGUGGUGAGCUGUCUGUGAGCACUGACAAGAGCUGGGGUCUUCAUCUGUGCAGCUGUAGCCCUCCUGGAGGUGGAUUGUGGGUCGAGGUCUAUGCUAAUCAUGUGCUUCUUAUGAGUGAUGGGAAGUGUGGCUGUCCUUGGUGUGCUCUGAAUGGAAAGGCAGAAGACCGGGAAUCACAGAGCCCAUCCUCAUCAGCUUCCAGGCAGAAGAACAUUUGGAAAACAACUAGUGAAGCAGCGUUAAGUGUUGUUAAUGAAAAAACACAGGCUGUUGUUAAUGAAAAAACACAGGCGCCUCUGGAUUGUGAUAACAGUGCUGAUAGAAUUCCCCACAAACCUUUCAUUAUAAUCGCAAGGGCCUGGAGCAGUGGUGGCCCCAGGUUCCAUCACAGGCGGCUGUGUGCUACUGGGACCGCAGACAGCACAUUCUCUGCUCUUCUCCAGCUCCAGGGCACCACUUCUGCAGCAGCUCCCUGCAGCCUGAAGAUGGAGGCUUCCUGCUGUGUCCUGAGACUGCUGUGCUGUGCGGAGGAUGUGGCCACGGGGCUGCUUCCUGGGACUGUCACGAUGGAGACCCCCACCAAGGUGGCCAGACCCACUCAGACCAGCUCCCAGCGAGUGCCCCUGUGGCCGAUUUCACAUUUUCCCACUUCUCCCAGAAGCUCCCACGGCCUUCCGCCUGGCAUUCCUCGCACCCCCAGCUUCACGGCAUCGCAGUCUGGUUCUGAGAUCCUCUAUCCCCCUACUCAGCAUCCUCCUGUGGCCAUCCUAGCUCGAAAUUCUGAUAACUUCAUGAACCCUGUUCUUAAUUGCUCCCUGGAAGUGGAAGCUCGGGCACCUCCAAAUCUGGGAUUCCGUGUUCAUAUGGCUUCUGGAGAGGCUCUCUGUCUGAUGAUGGAUUUCGGGGACAGUUCUGGGGUUGAAAUGAGGCUACACAACAUGUCUGAGGCAAUGGCGGUGACUGCCUACCACCAGUACUCAAAAGGUAUUUUUUUUCAUCUUUUACAUUUUCAGUUGGAUAUGUCCACCUACAAAGAAGCAGAGACACAAAAUACAACUUUAAAUGUUUACUUGUGCCAAAGUGAAAACAGCUGCCUGGAAGACUCAGACCCCAGUAACCUUGGAUAUGAGCUUAUUUCUGCCUUUGUCACCAAAGGAGUCUAUAUGCUCAAGGCUGUUAUUUAUAACGAGUUUCAUGGAACCGAAGUGGAGCUUGGGCCUUAUUAUGUGGAGAUUGGCCAUGAGGCCGUGUCUGCGUUCAUGAACUCCAGCAGUGUCCAUGAAGAUGAAGUGCUUGUCUUUGCUGACUCCCAAGUGAAUCAGAAAAGCACUGUGGUUAUACAUCACUUUCCAUCUAUUCCUUCAUAUAACGUGUCCUUUAUUUCUCAGACUCAAGUGGGUGACAGCCAGGCUUGGCACAGCAUGACUGUCUGGUAUAAGAUGCAAUCCGUCUCUGUCUACACAAAUGGAACUGUGUUUGCCACAGACACAGACAUUACAUUUACAGCUGUUACCAAGGAAACAAUACCCCUGGAAUUUGAGUGGUAUUUUGGAGAGGAUCCACCAGUGAGGACAACUUCAAGAAGCAUUAAAAAAAGACUCAGCAUCCCCCAAUGGUAUCGUGUGAUGGUUAAGGCUUCCAACAGGAUGAGCAGUGUGGUCUCUGAGCCCCAUGUCAUCAGGGUGCAGAAGAAAAUUGUGGCCAAUCGGCUCACGUCCCCCUCCUCAGCUCUGGUAAAUGCCAGUGUGGCCUUUGAGUGCUGGAUCAACUUCGGCACAGAUGUUGCCUACCUGUGGGACUUUGGGGAUGGCACCGUCAGCCUGGGGAGCAGCUCCAGCAGCCAUGUCUACAGUAGGGAAGGAGAAUUUACAGUGGAGGUCCUUGCCUUCAAUAAUGUCAGUGCCUCCACUCUAAGACAGCAACUUUUCAUCGUGUGCGAGCCCUGCCAGCCACCCCUGGUGAAGAACAUGGGGCCUGGGAAAGUCCAGAUAUGGAGGUCUCAGCCUGUGAGGCUGGGAGUGACGUUUGAAGCUGCAGUCUUCUGUGAUAUUUCCCAAGGUCUUUCUUACACCUGGAACUUGAUGGACUCUGAAGGGCUCCCUGUCUCCCUCCCUGCUGCUGUGGACACUCACAGACAGACCCUCAUCCUCCCGAGCCACACCUUGGAGUAUGGGAACUACACUGCCCUUGCCAAGGUUCAGAUUGAAGGCAGUGUGGUGUACAGCAACUACUGUGUGGGCCUGGAGGUGCGAGCCCAGGCCCCUGUCAGUGUGAUCUCCGAGGGCACACACCUAUUCUUCUCCAGGACCACCUCAUCCCCCAUUGUCCUCAGAGGGACCCAGUCCUUCGACCCUGACGACCCUGGGGCGACUCUCAGGUAUCACUGGGAAUGCGCCACCGCUGGCUCCCCAGCACAUCCCUGCUUCGACUCCUCCACUGCACACCAACUGGAUGCCGCGGCUCCCACUGUUUCCUUUGAGGCACAAUGGCUCAGUGACAGCUAUGAUCAGUUCCUUGUGAUGCUGAGGGUCUCCAGUGGUGGCCGGAACUCUUCUGAGACCCGGGUGUUCCUGUCCCCCUACCCUGACUCGGCGUUCAGAUUCGUCCACAUCUCCUGGGUCAGCUUUAAAGACACCUUCGUCAACUGGAAUGACGAACUCUCUCUUCAAGCUAUGUGUGAGGACUGCAGUGAAAUACCGAAUCUGUCUUAUUCCUGGGAUCUCUUUUUAGUCAAUGCAACAGAAAAGAAUAGGAUAGAAGUUCCCUUCUGCAGAGUAGUGGGGCUGCUUGGCUCGCUGGGACUCGGUGCCAUUUCAGAGUCAUCACAGUUAAACCUGCUGCCCACUGAGCCUGGCACUGCAGAUCCUGAUGCAACGACCACACCAUUCUCACGGGAACCUUCACCCGUGACCCUUGGCCAACCUGCCACUUCAGCUCCAAGGGGAACCCCCACAGAGCCCAUGACUGGAGUCUACUGGAUUCCUCCUGCGGGGGACUCUGCAGUCCUGGGGGAGGCUCCAGAGGAAGGUUCACUAGACCUAGAGCCAGGGCCACAGAGCAAGGGAUCCCUGAUGACUGGCCGCUCUGAGAGAAGUCAGCCCACCCACAGCCCUGACCCUCACCUCUCUGAUUUUGAAGCCUAUUACAGUGACAUUCAAGAAGCAAUACCAUCGGGAGGAAGACAGCCAGCUAAGGACACCAGCUUUCCAGGAUCAGGACCUAGCUUGAGUGCCGAGGAGAGCCCUGGAGAUGGGGAUAACCUGGUGGACCCCUCCCUGUCUGCAGGCAGAGCCGAGCCUGUCCUCAUGAUUGACUGGCCCAAGGCCCUGCUGGGUCGAGCAGUUUUCCAAGGCUAUUCAUCCUCAGGUAUUACAGAACAGACAGUGACAAUCAAGCCAUACUCUCUGAGCAGUGGAGAGACGUACGUCCUGCAAGUGUCUGUGGCUUCGAAGCAUGGCUUACUGGGUAAAGCUCAGCUGUACUUGACAGUCAACCCGGCUCCUCGGGACAUGGCCUGUCAGGUGCAGCCCCACCAUGGUCUGGAAGCACACACCGUCUUCAGUGUCUUCUGCAUGUCUGGAAAACCGGACUUCCAUUAUGAAUUUAGUUACCAGAUAGGAAACACCUCCAAACACACUUUGUACCAUGGGAGAGACACCCAGUAUUAUUUUGUGUUGCCAGCUGGUGAGCACUUGGACAAUUACAAAGUCAUGGUUUCCACUGAAAUCACAGAUGGCAAAGGCUCCAAGGUCCAGCCGUGCACUGUGGUGGUGACUGUGCUGCCCCGCUACCAUGGAAAUGACUGUCUGGGCGAGGACCUGUAUAAUUCCAGCCUGAAAAACCUUUCUACCCUCCAGCUGAUGGGGAGUUACACAGAAAUCAGGAACUACAUCACUGUGAUCACCAGAAUCCUGAGUCGUUUGUCUAAGGAGGACAAAACUGCCUCCUGCAACCAAUGGUCACGAAUACAGGAUGCAUUAAUUUCUUCAGUAUGCAGAUUGGCUUUUGUAGAUCAGGAAGAAAUGAUUGGUUCUGUUCUUAUGUUGAGGGACCUCGUGAGCUUCUCUAAUAAGCUAGGCUUUAUGAGUGCGGUUCUCAUCCUCAAGUACACCCGGGCACUCCUUGCUCAAGGCCAGUUCUCGGGGCCAUUUGUGAUUGACAAAGGAGUGAGGCUUGAGCUCAUCGGUCUCAUAUCCAGAGUCUGGGAAGUCUCUGAGCAAGAAAACUCGAAGGAGGAAGUCUAUCGACAUGAAGAAGGAAUUACAGUCAUCUCAGAUUUAUUGUUGGGUUGUCUCUCUUUGAACCAUGUUAGCACUGGGCAGAUGGAGUUCCGGACCCUUCUUCAUUACAACCUUCAGAGCUCUGUCCAGAGCCUGGGAUCUGUCCAGGUGCAUUUACCUGGUGACCUUGCUGGGCACAGUCCUGCUGGGGCGGAGACACAGAGCCCAUGCUACAUUAGCCAGCUCAUACUCUUCAAGAAGAACCCAUAUCCAGGGAGCCAAGCUCCUGGGCAGAUUGGUGGAGUUGUGGGCCUCAACCUCUAUACCUGCUCCAGCAGAAGACCCAUCAACAGGCAAUGGCUAAGGAAACCCGUGAUGGUCGAGUUUGGGGAGGAGGAUGGCCUGGAUAAUAGGAGAAAUAAAACGACAUUUGUAUUACUUCGGGAUAAAGUGAAUCUCCAUCAGUUCACUGAGCUUUCCGAAAACCCCCAGGAAUCUCUACAGAUAGAAAUUGAAUUUUCCAAACCUGUUACAAGGGCAUUUCCCGUCAUGUUGCUAGUAAGAUUCUCUGAGAAACCUACUCCCUCUGAUUUUCUUGUGAAGCAGAUCUACUUCUGGGAUGAGUCAAUUGUGCAGAUUUAUAUACCUGCUGCUUCUCAGAAAGAUGCCAGUGUAGGCUAUUUAUCCUUAUUGGAUGCUGACUAUGACAGAAAACCUCCAAACAGAUAUUUAGCUAAGGCAGUGAACUAUACAGUACAUUUCCAGUGGAUCCGAUGCCUGUUUUGGGACAAGAGAGAGUGGAAAUCUGAACGUUUCUCUCCACAACCAGGGACUUCUCCUGAAAAAGUGAACUGCAGCUACCAUCGCCUCGCGGCAUUCGCUCUCCUAAGGAGAAAGCUGAAGGCCAGUUUUGAAGUGAGUGACAUUUCCAAGCUACAGAGCCACCCAGAAAACUUGCUUCCCAGUAUUUUUAUUAUGGGUUCUGUGAUUCUUUAUGGAUUUUUGGUCGCUAAAAGUAGACAAGUAGAUCAUCAUGAAAAAAAGAAAGCUGGUUACAUCUUUCUGCAAGAAGCUUCCCUGCCGGGCCAUCAGCUAUAUGCGGUCGUCAUUGACACUGGCUUCCGAGCUCCGGCCAGGUUGACCUCAAAGGUGUACAUUGUUUUAUGUGGCGACAAUGGACUGUCAGAAACCAAGGAGCUCUCCUGUCCAGAGAAGCCCCUGUUUGAAAGGAAUUCCAGACACACCUUUAUCCUGAGCGCUCCUGCCCAACUGGGCCUGCUGAGGAAGAUCCGCCUCUGGCACGACAGCCGUGGGCCUUCCCCAGGCUGGUUCAUCAGCCACGUGAUGGUGAAGGAGCUGCACACGGGACAGGGCUGGUUCUUCCCUGCCCAGUGCUGGCUGUCUGCCGGCAGGCAUGAUGGUCGCGUGGAGCGGGAGCUCACCUGUCUGCAAGGGGGACUCGGCUUCCGGAAGCUUUUCUAUUGCAAGUUCACAGAGUACCUGGAGGAUUUCCAUGUCUGGCUGUCGGUGUACAGCAGGCCCUCCUCCAGCCGCUACCUGCACACGCCGCGCCUCACCGUGUCCUUCUCCCUGCUGUGCGUCUACGCGUGUCUCACUGCCCUGGUUGCUGCUGGAGGGCAAGAGCAGCCCCACUUGGACGUCAGCCCCACCCUUGGAUCCUUCAGGGUGGGUCUCCUGUGUACCCUCCUGGCUUCUCCAGGGGCCCAGCUCUUGUCCCUGCUCUUCAGGCUCAGCAAGGAAGCCCCGGGGUCUGCCCGAGUGGAGCCACACAGCCCACUUAGAGGAGGAGCACAGACCGAGGCACCCCAUGGUCCUAAUUCCUGGGGAAGGAUACCAGACGCACAGGAGCCACGCAAGCAACCUGCAUCAGCCAUUCUCUCUGGGAGUGGCAGGGCCCAAAGGAAGGCGGCAAGUGACAAUGGCACAGCUUGUCCAGCCCCUAAGCUGCAGGUUCAUGGGGCUGACCACAGCAGGACUUCUCUGAUGGGGAAAAGCCACUGCUGCCCUCCCCACACUCAAGCACCCAGCAGUGGUUUGGAGGGACUAAUGCCCCAGUGGUCAAGGGCCCUUCAGCCUUGGUGGAGCUCUGCAGUGUGGGCCAUUUGUGGGACCGCUUCUUUGGCCUGCAGUUUGGGGACAGGAUUUCUAGCCUACAGGUUUGGCCAGGAGCAAUGUGUGCAGUGGCUGCACCUGCUGUCCCUCUCCGUGGUCUGCUGUAUUUUCAUCACCCAGCCACUUAUGGUAUGCCUCAUGGCCUUGGGUUUUGCUUGGAAAAGAAGAGCUGACAACCACUUUUUUACUGAGUCUUUAUGUGAGGCUACCAGGGAUCUGGACUCUGAAUUGGCAGAACGUUCCUGGACUCGCCUCCCCUUCUCUUCAAGCUGCAGUAUUCCUGACUGUGCAGGCGAGGUUGAAAAAGUCUUGGCUGCCCGACAACAAGCUCGCCACCUGCGCUGGGCGCAUCCACCAUCCAAGGCCCAGCUGAGGGGCACCAGACAGAGGAUGAGGAGAGAGAGUCGCACACGGGCUGCCCUGAGAGACAUUUCCAUGGACAUCCUCAUGCUGCUUCUGCUUUUGUGUGUAAUAUAUGGGAGAUUUUCCCAAGAUGAAUACUCCCUCAAUCAAGCUAUCCGGAAAGAAUUUACAAGAAAUGCCAGAAACUGCUUGGGUGGCCUGAGAAACAUCGCUGACUGGUGGGACUGGAGUCUGACCACACUUCUGGAUGGCCUGUACCCGGGAGGCACCCCGUCAGCCCGUGUGCCGGGGGCUCAGCCUGGAGCUCUUGGAGGAAAAUGCUACCUAAUAGGCAGUUCCGUAAUUAGGCAGCUAAAAGUUUUUCCUAGGCAUUUAUGCAAGCCUCCCAGGCCAUUUUCAGCACUCAUCGAAGACUCUAUUCCUACAUGUAGUCCCGAAGUUGGAGGCCCUGAGAACCCCUACCUGAUAGACCCAGAGAACCAAAACGUGACCCUGAAUGGUCCUGGGGGCUGUGGGACAAGGGAGGACUGUGUGCUCAGCCUGGGCAGAACAAGGACUGAAGCCCACACAGCCCUGUCCCGACUCAGGGCCAGCAUGUGGAUUGACCGCAGCACCAGGGCUGUGUCUGUGCACUUCACUCUCUAUAACCCUCCAACCCAACUCUUCACCAGCGUGUCCCUGAGAGUGGAGAUCCUCCCUACGGGGAGUCUCGUCCCCUCAUCCCUGGUGGAGUCAUUCAGCAUCUUCCGCAGCGACUCAGCCCUGCAGUACCACCUCAUGCUUCCCCAGCUGGUCUUCCUGGCACUCAGCCUGAUCCACCUCUGUGUUCAACUCUACCGUAUGAUGGACAAGGGCGUCCUCAGCUACUGGCGAAAGCCAAGGAACUGGCUGGAGCUCUCCGUGGUUGGAGUGAGCCUCACCUACUAUGCAGUUUCCGGCCACCUUGUUACUCUUGCUGGAGAUGUCACUAACCAGUUUCACAGAGGACUUUGCCGAGCAUUUAUGGACCUCACCCUUAUGGCAUCAUGGAAUCAGAGGGCUCGAUGGCUCCGGGGAAUCCUCUUAUUCCUCUUCACAUUAAAAUGCGUCUAUCUUCCUGGCAUUCAAAACACAAUGGCAUCCUGCUCCUCCAUGAUGCGCCACUCACUCCCCAGCAUCUUUGUAGCAGGGCUGGUGGGGGCACUGAUGCUGGCCGCCCUCUCCCACCUGCACCGAUUUCUGCUCUCUAUGUGGGUUCUACCACCUGGCACCUUCACAGACGCCUUCCCCGGGCUGCUGUUUCAUUUUCCCAGAAGAAGCCAAAAAGACUGCCUCCUUGGCCUUUCCAAGUCUGACCAGCGGGCCAUGGCUUGUUACUUUGGGAUCCUUUUAAUAGUCUCUGCCACACUGUGUUUUGGAAUGCUGAGAGGUUUUCUCAUGACUUUACCCCAAAAAAGAAAAUCUUUUCAAAGUAAAUCUUUUGUGAGACUUAAAGAUGUCACUGCUUAUAUGUGGGAAAAGGUCCUCACCUUUCUGAGACUGGAAACACCAAAGUUGGAAGAGGCUGAGAUGGUUGAGAAUCACAAUUACUACUUGGAUGAAUUUGCAAAUCUGUUAGACGAACUUCUGAUGAAGAUUAAUGGUUUGUCCGACAGCCUACAACUCCCCCUUCUGGAAAAAACAUCCAACAACACAGGGGAGGCAAGGACAGAAGAGAGUCCCUUAGUGGACAUUUCUAGUUACCAAGCUGCUGAGGAAAACACAACGCUUUCUGGACUAUCACUUUAUGAGCCAGCAGACAUCAAGGACUUCUGAGGAGCCUGGUACCUUGCAUAGGCACUAUGGACCCUGUUUUGCUUAACCCACCCAACAGCCAAUUUUAGCAGACAUCCUAGUUUUGCAGGUGAGAAGAGCUGAGGUACGAAGAAGUUUUGUUAAUUUUUCCAGUUCACGUAACAAGUAAAUGGGAAACCAGGAUGAAAAUCAAGGUUUAUCUGUCAUCAGACUGUUACUCAUAAUCACCAUUCGGAGAGUUCAGAUGUGGGACAAGAUUCUAACUCCAGCCUUCUCCCAAAUGGUUAAUUUGCCAGUUGCCCUAGAGUUACAUAUUGUCUUAUUUGUUUGUUUUACUGAAUCUGUCUGAGUAUUAAAAGCCUUGUAUCUUGUGAAAUUUCUUUCAGGUCUCAUAAAAGCGAUGAAAGAGACCAGGAUAACAUUCUAAUAUUUAAAUAAGAUUUUUGAAGUAAAAUCCUUAUUUUGUAAAUUUAACAAUUGAAUCUUGCUAGAUUAAUAACGCAUCUUUCCUGAUUUACUAAUUCAAUAUAAAAUGGUUAUUCAAACUGAA